CUGGCAGUGUCAUGGCUGCCCACAGGUCUGCAGGCACUCGGUACGCCGCUAACGCGGCGAGGUAGCUCGGUGCGUCUCGCGGUACCAGUGCGAAUCAUCGGGCUAUCCAGGUCCGAGAUCCUAGUCUCCUGUCGGCUCUGAGGAGGAUGGAUCCUUCUGCGGAUACAUGGGACCUCUUCUCACCUUUAAUAUCAUUAUGGAUAAACAGGUUUUACAUUUAUUUGGGCUUUGCUGUUAGCAUUAGCCUUUGGAUUUGUGUCCAGAUUGUCAUCAAGACGCAGGGCAAGAACUUACAGGAAAAAUCUGUUCCAAAAGCAGCUCAGGAUUUGAUGACAAAUGGUUAUGUCUCCCUUCAAGAGAAAGACAUCUUUGUGUCUGGAGUGAAGAUUUUUUAUGGUUCUCAGACUGGAACAGCGAAGGGAUUCGCAACAGUUCUUGCUGAAGCAGUUACAUCCCUGGAUCUGCCUGUGGCCAUUAUUAAUCUAAAAGAAUAUGAUCCAGAUGAUCAUCUGAUAGAAGAGGUGACUAGUAAAAAUGUCUGUGUCUUCCUGGUUGCGACAUACACUGACGGCCUACCAACUGAAAGUGCAGAGUGGUUCUGCAAAUGGUUAGAGGAAGCAUCCAUUGAUUUUCGAUUUGGCAAAACUUACCUGAAGGGUAUGAGAUAUGCGGUAUUUGGCCUGGGAAAUUCUGCCUAUGCUAGCCACUUCAACAAGGUUGGCAAAAAUGUUGACAAGUGGCUCUGGAUGCUUGGCGCGCAUCGUGUGAUGAGUCGAGGGGAGGGCGACUGCGACGUGGUUAAAAGCAAGCACGGCAGCAUUGAGGCCGACUUCAGAGCAUGGAAGACCAAGUUCAUCUCCCAGCUGCAGGCACUUCAGAAAGGGGAGAGAAAGAAGUCCUGUGGCGGCCACUGCAAGAAAGGCAAAUGUGAAUCUCACCAACAUGGCUCAGAGGAGAGGGAGGAAGGAUCUCAUGAGCAGGAUGAAUUGCAUCAUAGAGACACCGAGGAGGAAGAACCCUUUGAGAGCUCCAGUGAAGAAGAGUUUGGUGGUGAGGACCAUCAGAGCCUAAAUUCCAUUGUUGAUGUUGAAGAUUUGGGCAAAAUUAUGGAUCAUGUGAAGAAAGAAAAGAGAGAAAAGGAACAGCAGGAAGAGAAGUCUGGUUUGUUCAGGAACAUGGGGAGGAAUGAAGAUGGUGAAAGAAGAGCUAUGAUAACUCCUGCUCUCCGAGAAGCCCUUACUAAACAAGGUUAUCAGUUGAUUGGGAGCCACUCGGGGGUGAAGCUUUGCAGGUGGACAAAGUCCAUGCUCCGAGGGAGAGGAGGUUGUUACAAACACACAUUCUAUGGAAUUGAGAGCCAUCGCUGCAUGGAAACCACCCCGAGCUUGGCGUGUGCUAAUAAAUGUGUCUUCUGUUGGCGGCACCACACCAACCCCGUGGGCACUGAGUGGCGGUGGAAGAUGGACCAGCCUGAAAUGAUCUUGAAGGAAGCCAUUGAAAACCAUCAGAACAUGAUUAAGCAGUUUAAAGGAGUACCGGGCGUCAAAGCAGAACGCUUUGAAGAAGGAAUGACGGUAAAGCACUGUGCAUUGUCCCUCGUGGGAGAACCAAUAAUGUACCCAGAGAUCAACAGGUUUUUGAAGCUACUCCACCAGUGUAAAAUUUCCAGCUUCCUGGUCACAAACGCACAAUUUCCUGCGGAAAUCAGGAACCUCGAGCCGGUUACUCAGCUGUAUGUCAGUGUGGAUGCCAGUACCAAAGACAGCCUGAAGAAAAUCGACCGCCCACUCUUCAAGGAUUUCUGGCAGAGAUUCCUUGACAGUUUAAAAGCCUUGGCAGUCAAGCAACAACGAACUGUCUACAGACUGACGCUCGUGAAAGCAUGGAACGUGGACGAGCUCCAGGCCUACGCGCAGCUCGUGUCCCUGGGGAAUCCUGACUUCAUCGAAGUGAAGGGCGUUACCUACUGCGGAGAAAGUUCAGCAAGCAGUCUUACCAUGGCCCACGUGCCCUGGCAUGAGGAAGUGGUACAGUUUGUCCACGAGUUGGUGGAUCUGAUCCCCGAAUAUGAAAUUGCAUGUGAACACGAACACUCUAAUUGCCUCCUGAUAGCACACAGAAAGAUGGUCCAGGUUUCCUUUGGAAUCUUCCCCAUCUGUUUGAAGAACUUCCUUUAGCAAUUCUCUUAGAGCCAGUGUGAUAGCAACCAGUCCUCUUAGUUUUCCUUCAUCUGCCACUGUCUUGGUUUCCUCUCCAUUCCUGAAGGAUGUUUUUGGCAGGUAAAGUAUUCUGGAUUGACAGCUCUUUUCUUUCCUUCUGGCUUCUCUGGUAUCUGAUGAAAAAUUCUUUGUCAUUUGAUUGUUUUUCUCCUUUAGGUAAGAUGUUUCUCUCCCUGCUUUCAAGAUUUUUAAAAAUAUUCAGGUCUUGAGUUUUCAGAAGUUUGAUUACAGGUUGCCUUGGACUGGAUUUCUUUGGGUCUGUUGUUUUGGAGGCAUGCUCAGCUUCCUGAAUCUGCAGGUAUAUGCCCUUUACAAAUUGGGGGAAUUUCUAGUUGUUCUCCAGAUACUUUUUUCAGCCUCAUCUUAUUUCUCUUUUCUUUUUAGAUCUCUGAUGACACAAAUGUUAGAUUUUUUUUUGUUAUGGUCCCACAGGUAUCUGAGGCUUUGUUUGUUUCUCUUUUAGUCUCUCUGUUUUUUAGACUCUUGUUCUAACUUUAGAUUGAUUCAUUCUGUCUUUUUACUCUUCCAUUCUGUUGAACCAUUUAUUAUUUUAGUUAUUGUAUUUUUCAGUUCUAAAAUUUCCAUUUGAUUAUUUUCCUAUUUCUAUUUAACUAUUUCUCCUUCCUCCCUCCCUUCCUUCCUUCCUCCCUCCCUUCCUUCUUCUCUUUUUUUAUUUUCCUUCUUCUUCUUCCUCUUCCUCUUCCUCUUCUUCUUCUUCUUCUUUCUUCUUCCUUCUUCCUUCUUUCUUCUUCUUCUUUUCUUUUUUUUUUUGAGAGAGAGAAUCUCACUCUGUCAUCCAGGCUGGAAUCCAAUGGCACAAUCUCGGCUCACUGCAACCUCCACCUCCGAGUUCAAGUGAUUCUCCUGCCUCAGCCUCCUGAGUAGCUGGGAUUACAGGCGUGUACCACCAUGCCCAGCUAAUUUUCUCAUUUUUAUUAGAGAUGGGGUUUCACCAUGUUGGCCAGGCUGGUCUUGAACUCCUGGCUUCCAGUGAUCCACCCACCUCCACCUCCCUGGGAUUACAGGCAUGAGCCACCACGCCCAGCCAACUUUCUAUUUAUCAUGUCCGUUUUUAAUUGCCCAUUGAAGCACAUUUGUGAUGGCUACUUUAAAAUCUUAAUCAGAUAAUACCAACGCACAUACCACGUUGGCAUCUUUUGAUUGUCUUUUCUCAUUCAAGUUGAGAUUUUCCUGUUUCUUGGUAUGAUAAGUGAUUUUCAGUUGUUUCCCAGACAUUUUGGGUGUUAUGUUAGGAGACUCUGGAUCUUAUUUAUUAAUAAAUCUUCUGUCUUAGCCAGCCUCCUUUGACACUGCACUGUGGGGAUGGCAUGAGAGGGUGUUACCUCCUUACUUCCAGGGAGAGGUAAAAGUCCAUUUCCCCCCUCAGCUUCUAUUGACCUAUUGUAGGAAGGGUGCCUUGUUACUGCCAAGUAGGGGCAGAAGUUCUGGCUCCCGUCAGCCUCCUGUGAUACCAUUCUGAUGAGGAAGGGAGAGCCAUCUUGUGACUGUUCCCCCCUUAGACUCCACUGACAUUAUAGGAUGGAGGCGGGGGGGGGGCCUUAUUGCUGCUGGGUGGUGGCAGAAGUCCUGGUUCUCCACUAAGCUUCUUCUGACACCACUCAAGUGUAUGGGGGAGAGGUGCCUUGUUACUGCUAGGUGGAGUGAAAGUCCAGGCUCCCUGUGUAGUCUGUAUGACAUUACAGCUGGAGGGGAGGAGGAGGGCAGGAUUCCCCGCUCACCUUCUCUGAUACCGCCCUGGUAGUAGGAGUCAAGAAGAGUGCCUCAUUAUAACCAGGUGAAGGUGGGAAUCUAGGUUCCCCACUCAGUAUUUGCUGACCGGAUGGGAAUGAGGCCCGUUUUUCUCAUGGCCUAGGUUGGUUAUUGUCUAAAAAUUUUCUGUCUUGCUAGGCUGCCCUGUUCCUGCUGUCCUAAGAGAGCAGCCUUUACUUGGGACUCUUUUUUUUUUAAUCCAAUAAUUGUCCGCAGCCAUUGGUGUUUCUGGCUUGCAGCCCAGUCCAGGAUAUCUGAGCCAAAAAUAAAACUCAAGAAAGCCACCACCAUGUUGUUCCUCAGAUCCCAAGGCCCCUAGCCAGUGUGCCUUCUUAUCUCUACCUUUGAGAAUCUUUUUGCUUGCCUUAUAUGUAAUAUCCUCUAUUUUUAGCUGUACUUAGCAGGCAGAAUAGGGAGAGGCACGUCUACUCCAUCUUGUCCAGAACCAGACAUUAUACCACUGUAGAGUUGGGGUUCACAUCUCCUAGUGAACAGUAAUGCCAAUCCAGAUGGGACUAUUUGAUAUUGGUAGAUUAUUUCCAGGUGAACUCAUUUUCUUUAUUUAAUUGAAAGGUGUCGCCCAGUUAAGGUUGUAUGGCUGCUCUUGCAGUGUUACUGGAAAGAAUUUCCUGACACAUGAAAACAUCUUUUCCUAAUCCUAAUCAGAUCUCAUCAGAUCCCAUUUAAUAAAUGGCUAGCAAUUUACUCUAAGGGUACUAGUGUUGAAAAGCAGAGAUGUGGCCAGGCACGGUGGCUCACACCUGUAAUCUCAGCACUUUGGGACGCCAAGGCAGGUGGAUCACCUUAGGUCAGGAGUUCGAGACCAGCCUGGCCAACAUGGUGAAACCCCAUCUUUACUAAAAAUACAAAACUUAGCUGGGUGUGGUGGCUGGCACCUGUAAUCACAACUACUUGGGAGGCGGAGGCAGAAGAAUUGCUUGAACCUGGGAGGCAGAGGUUGCAGUGAGCCAAGAUCGUGCCACUGGGCGACAAAAUGAGACUCUGUCUCAAACAUAAAUAAAUAAAUAAAUAAAUAAAUAAAUAAAUAAAUAAAUAAAAUGAAGCAGAGAUGUAACUAAAAGACAAGGGAAAGAAGCAGAAAAGGAGCAAAACAAACCCUAAAGACUAGAAGAAUACACUAAAAUGAUCAUACAAUCCAUACAUAACCGAGGGCAGAUAUCAACUACUCAACAUCUUCCUUGUUUAUGCCGCUAAUUCCAAGCUUAUUGUUUCUCUACAUUUUGGAACAUGUGACAUAUCACAUAACAUGCAAGAGAAACACCUAAUCAUUUUAUUGGAUUUGUAAUGGCCUUCACAAUCGGUUCCUUUUUCACUUCAUUUCAUGCUCCCUCCCUGGGCUUUUAAACGGUACUGCCAUAUUCCUUCUUUCUUCUGUGCAUUUAUUUGCUCAAGGUAUUUCUUUGGCCAGAAACGCCCUCCUUUCCCUACCCACCCCAAUUCACCUUGUGUAGUUCCACUCUUUAAAAUUGUAAAACAAACUUCUUUUCCUUUGAGACUACUUCUGUCAGAUCUGUAUGUACAUAUACCAAGCAUGCCUCCUCCAGGAAGCUGUGAGUUCCUAGAACACCAGGACCGUUACUCCCAGUACUUUCUAGAGUAACUGGUACAUAUCAGAUUCUCCGUGUGCUUAGUGGAUCAAUAGCCCCCUUUCCUUCAUCCGCUUUCCUUUCUCAUUGUCUUCCCUUCUGGAAUCAGAAACUUUGUUCCAUCUUCUUUGCUAGUUUUGGUACCUACCAACCUUCUUCCUUAUCAUUCAUUCACUCCAUUUAUUCAGUAAAUAUUUACCAGGCUGAGUUUGCUAUUUUGUAUGUCAUCAGUGACCUGCUAAUUGUUAAAUCCAGUGACCUUUUCUCAUUCACCAUACCUUCCUUUUUCUGCAGCAGGAAACUGAUGCCAUCCAUGCUUGGUGAAAGUCAUCCCUAUCUACUGUACUGUACUUUUUUGAUUAUAGUAAAAUUGGCUAGCAGAAAUAAGAAUAUUGUUACAAAGUAGAACAUUGAAAAUUCCCCAGUUGUGACAUUUGUUUAUCUACUUCACAAAUUUUGUUUGCCUUUUUUUUUUUUG